AGAGUCAGGGCCACGGAGCUUAGGAGACCUUGGGUCAGCUCUGCAAAGGGGUUGUUUACUGAAUGCUUCUGGUAUCUGCAGCCCCGCUGGGGUUCGGACAGGGGGUCUGGAAUAGGGCUUCACAACUACAGCAGGGCUAGGACCCUCUUGGGCUGGAAGGAGCUGGAGAGGCCUCUGCAAGCUGUCACAGGCUCUUGGUGCUGGCACUGGCUCAGGCUUUCACACACACACACGCGCACACACACACACACACACACACGGACAGGCACCCCCUUGGUGGCCUUCACAGUUUCACCUUCAGGCUCAAAGCUGGCUCUGCAGGGGACAUGAGAGGCACACCGAAGACCCACCUCCUGGCCUUCUCCCUCCUCUGCCUCCUCUCAAAGGUGCGUACCCAGCUGUGCCCGACACCAUGUACCUGCCCCUGGCCACCUCCCCGAUGCCCGCUGGGAGUACCCCUGGUGCUGGAUGGCUGUGGCUGCUGCCGGGUAUGUGCACGGCGGCUGGGGGAGCCCUGCGACCAACUCCACGUCUGCGACGCCAGCCAGGGCCUGGUCUGCCAGCCCGGGGCAGGACCCGGUGGCCGGGGGGCCCUGUGCCUCUUGGCAGAGGACGACAGCAGCUGUGAGGUGAACGGCCGCCUGUAUCGGGAAGGGGAGACCUUCCAGCCCCACUGCAGCAUCCGCUGCCGCUGCGAGGACGGCGGCUUCACCUGCGUGCCGCUGUGCAGCGAGGAUGUGCGGCUGCCCAGCUGGGACUGCCCCCACCCCAGGAGGGUCGAGGUCCUGGGCAAGUGCUGCCCUGAGUGGGUGUGCGGCCAAGGAGGGGGACUGGGGACCCAGCCCCUUCCAGCCCAAGGACCCCAGUUUUCUGGCCUUGUCUCUUCCCUGCCCCCUGGUGUCCCCUGCCCAGAAUGGAGCACGGCCUGGGGACCCUGCUCGACCACCUGUGGGCUGGGCAUGGCCACCCGGGUGUCCAACCAGAACCGCUUCUGCCGACUGGAGACCCAGCGCCGCCUGUGCCUGUCCAGGCCCUGCCCACCCUCCAGGGGUCGCAGUCCACAAAACAGUGCCUUCUAGAGCCGGGCUGGGAAUGGGGACACGGUGUCCACCAUCCCCAGCUGGUGGCCCUGUGCCUGGGCCCUGGGCUGAUGGAAGAUGGUCCGUGCCCAGGCCCUUGGCUGCAGGCAACACUUUAGCUUGGGUCCACCAUGCAGAACACCAAUAUUAACACGCUGCCUGGUCUGUCUGGAUCCCGAGGUAUGGCAGAGGUGCAAGACCUAGUCCCCUUUCCUCUAACUCACUGCCUAGGAGGCUGGCCAAGGUGUCCAGGGUCCUCUAGCCCACUCCCUGCCUACACACACAGCCUAUAUCAAACAUGCACACGGGCGAGCUUUCUCUCCGACUUCCCCUGGGCAAGAGAUGGGACAAGCAGUCCCUUAAUAUUGAGGCUGCAGCAGGUGCUGGGCUGGACUGGCCAUUUUUCUGGGGGUAGGAUGAAGAGAAGGCACACAGAGAUUCUGGAUCUCCUGCUGCCUUUUCUGGAGUUUGUAAAAUUGUUCCUGAAUACAAGCCUAUGCGUGA